AGAAUCCUCUGAAGAGUUGCUGAGGCAGAACUGAAAUCAUGGCUCACCUCAAAGAAGCAGCAGUAUUGGCCGUUAAUGAUGCCUCACACAGAAAGACGAUGCUCCUUUAACUCGGGGUUUUAAUGGGAAGUUUCUAAGCCUGAAACAACAGCUUUAGACCUGGGGUGUGCCAUCAGCUGCCUUGCAGCUACCACUGUCUACUGCUUUCACACAGCGUGGUCGGGAAGAAUGGAAACUAAAGAGGCUUGUAACUACCUGUAACUGUUCCACCAGGAAAUGGAUCAAGUGUUUGUUCAGCCAGAGCCAGUAUUAAAAUUAGACUCUAUUUCCUGAGCACCCACAAAUGGACCUGACAAAGGGAAGACACAGAUGUACUGCGUGAUGAGGAAAGCCUAUCAGGAUUAAAAUAUGGCUAUAACUCAGCCUCUCCAGAGUGCAGCCACCAUGACCUCCGCAGAUUGAUGAUGGAAGAAAAGAAAACCAGGAUAUCCUGUGCUCUGGCUUCCCUGGACCAUGGAUGGAGGACAGCCCAUCCCCUCAUCCCUAGUGCCCCUUGGGAACGAAUCAGCAGAUUCUAGCAUGUCCCUGGAGCAGAAAAUGACAUUUGUUUUUGUGAUUCUGUUGUUUAUUUUCUUGGGCAUUCUCAUUGUCCGGUGCUUCCGGAUUCUUUUGGAUCCAUAUCGAAGCAUGCCAACCUCUACCUGGGCUGAUGGACUUGAAGGCCUGGAGAAAGGGCAGUUCGACCAUGCCCUUGCUUAGGAGGGAUGGUGUGGGAUCUCCUCCUGAGGAGAUGAAGUGCUUUGUGUCUUGGUGAGGAUUCCCUUUAUUUAGUGUUCUCAACAAAUCAAAUUUAAACAAUAUUUGGUCCCAGGACCAUAAUCCAUUAUUCCAUAAAUAUGCAGUUGGGUUAAAGACAUUUGAGGAUGUUGGAAAUGGACACUUAUAUAACUAAUCCAACAUAAGAAGGUUUAAAUUUUUAUGUUUGCUCAAUGAAUGAGUACUCUUAAAAUUGUGUGAUUGUGAAACCAAGAGCGUUAAUACUGACAUAGAUUUGCCAUCAAACAAAACACCACCUGAUCUGACUAAAGAAUAAAAGACUAGAAAGGAUCUCAUAUGAAUCUGGUGACAAGGCCAGGAAGAGAUUUCCUUGCUCUAAUUAUGUCUAUAUUUGUUUUAUUUCAUGGGCACCUAUCUGGGUCCUGAGCAGAAUGAGGAAGAUUGUGCUGAAUGGACCCAAAGUAGUUUCUUGUUUUCUCCCAAAGCAGGGAGCUUUGGGAAGCAAUGGAAAAGCUUAAAAGAGAUGAUUCUGUCCUUGGUAAAUGUGAGUGAGAAUAGCGUUUUGUUUUUCAAGUAAAACUUAAUUCAAAGGCUACAAAGUUUUAAAAACUAUUUACCAAGCCAACUACAUUAUAUGUAUUCAUAUUAAUAACAUGUGUAGAGGUAGCUAUACAUUACUUGAAUUUACACUUUACACAAAUGAUUUAAAAAAUAGGUUGCAAGUGCAGCUUAAAGUUUUUUUUCAAUGAAAAGUUAAUUGUUUAGAGGAGAAGACUUUUAUAGUCUUCAGAGGAAUGUGUAUUUAUGAUUGUAUAUAGUCACCAAAUAAAACUUUUCAAGAAACA